GCUGAUGCGAACUGGGGCCACGGCAGCCAUCGCGCUUUGCAGUUCGGUCUCCUGGUGUACGGCCAACGCCAAGUAGGGGAUUGCGUUCCCUCCAGUCGCAGAGUUUCCCUCUUGUCGCCCAGGCUGGAGUGAAGUGGCACGAUCUCGGCUUACUGCAAGCUCCGCCUCCCGGGUUCACGCCAUUCUCCUGCCUCAGCCUCCCGAGUAGCUGGGACUACAGACCCUAUCAGAUUUGGAUAUGUCCUUCAUAUUUGAUUGGAUUUACAGUGGUUUCAGCAGUGUGCUACAGUUUUUAGGAUUAUAUAAGAAAACUGGUAAACUGGUAUUUCUUGGAUUGGAUAAUGCAGGAAAAACAACAUUGCUACACAUGCUAAAAGAUGACAGACUUGGACAACAUGUCCCAACAUUACAUCCCACUUCCGAAGAACUGACCAUUGCUGGCAUGACGUUUACAACUUUUGAUCUGGGUGGACAUGUUCAAGCUCGAAGAGUGUGGAAAAACUACCUUCCUGCUAUCAAUGGCAUUGUAUUUCUGGUGGAUUGUGCAGACCACGAAAGGCUGUUAGAGUCAAAAGAAGAACUUGAUUCACUAAUGACAGAUGAAACCAUUGCUAAUGUGCCUAUACUGAUUCUUGGGAAUAAGAUCGACAGACCUGAAGCCAUCAGUGAAGAGAGGUUGCGAGAGAUGUUUGGUUUAUAUGGUCAGACAACAGGAAAGGGGAGUAUAUCUCUGAAAGAACUGAAUGCCCGACCCUUAGAAGUUUUCAUGUGUAGUGUGCUCAAAAGACAAGGUUACGGAGAAGGCUUCCGCUGGAUGGCACAGUACAUUGAUUAACACAAACUCACAUUGGUUCCAGGUCUCAACGUUCAGGCUUACUCAGAGAUUUGAUUGCUCAACAUGCAUAACUUGAAUUCAAUAGACUUUUGCUGGUUAUAAAACAGAUGUUUUUUAGAUUAUUAAUAUUAAAUCAACUUAAUUUGAAUGAGAAUUGAAAACUGAUUCAAGUAAGUUUGAGUAUCACAAUGUUAGCUUUCUAAUUCCAUAAAAGUACUUGGUUUUUACAGUUUAUAAUCUGACAUCACCCCAGCGCCAUUUGUAAAGAGCAACUUUCCAGCAGUACAUUUGAAGCACUUUUUAACAACAUGAAACUAUAAACCAUAUUUAAAAGCUCAUCAUGUUAAAUUUUUUAUGUACUUUUCUGGAACUAGUUUUUAAAUUUUAGAUUAUAUGUCCACCUAUCUUAAGUGUACAGUUAAUAAUUAGCUUAUUCAAUGAUUGCAUGAUGCCUUACAGUUUUCAAUAACUUUUUUUCUUAUGCAAACGUCAUGCAAUAAAACAAACUCUAAUGUUUGGCAUCCUUGUUGGGCAAAUGUUUCAUUUAAAUGUGUCUUAUCUAGCUAGUAUACUCUGAAAAUUUGAGUAUUUAAUAUUAGGCAUAUGAAGUGGUUGUUGGGAAAGGAGAUUCCUUCAGAAUAUUUAGAAUAGCGUUUAAGGCUCUCAAGGCUUAGGUAUUUACCAUGAGAUGGUUGUGGUCAGUUGCACCUGAUACCAUGUAUCCCUGAAUCAUGUGUAUUUUUAUUAGUAAUGCAGCCACUACCAUUGCUGAUGGGGUCUGUGUCCUAGUCCCUGUGGGAUUGGCCUUCUGAAGAAAAGCACAUUUAUGGUACACAAGGUUGAUUCUCAGUUUGGUAGGCUCUAUAGUUCCAUCCCAGCUGUCUAAUUCUGAAGUGCUCCAGUCUUAUUGGUGCCCAAUGGGGUAAUCUGUGCCUCUUCCCCAAAAGCAAUGACAGGCACCAGUGUCUCCACAUUUAGAUAUAUUCCCAGUCUCUGUACAUUUAACAGUACUCUCUGGGGCAAGCAAUAAGUAGGACCUUGUGUGCAGUUUCAUUGUAGAGACAUGUAUAUCUGAGGAAUAAAACAGCUUGUUCUGUGUCAGUCUGAGAUAUGUGGAGAUUUUGUUCCUAUCCUAUAGCUCUUUUGUAUUCUUUGGCAUAUUUUAUAUCCUGGUAGAAGAAAACAAGUGCUUGUUUCCAAUUUUCUUUUUUCUUAUUUGCUCUCAGGUAGUUCUUACUCCAUACAACAAAGACUUUUUGUUUGUUGGGCUUUUUUUUUUUUUUUUUUUUUGCUCUGUUUCAUUUUGUUUUAGAGACGGGGUUUCACCAUGUUGUCCAGGCUGGUCUCAAACUCCUGACCUCAAGUGAUCUGCCCGCCUUGGCCUCCCAAAGUUCUGGGAUUAUAGGCGUGAGCUACCAUGCCUGACCUGACUUUUGUUUUUAGAUAUUAUGCUUGCCAUGUGAUAGGGCCUGCAAGCCUCAUUGCUAGGCUUACUAAGAAAAUUUUAGUUUUUCAAAAGCAUUAUAAUUUCCUAAGAAACUGAAUUCUUUUUUUAUAUGUUUGAGAUUCCCAUCAUUAGUAAUAUAAGAUGAAAGGUAAGUGCCAAAAAUGUAUUUUUAAAGACCCUCAAGUUUAAGAUUUAUCCUGAUUAUAAGCCAAGUUUUAUAGUAUAUUUAACCAAUUCCAUCAAGAAUAAUUUUAAUAUCAAAAAUUAGUGUUUUCUGUAGCCAUUGUCCAUGUCAGAGUUACAGUCCUUUUUGUCAUUGAUAAUAUAACCUAUGAAGCAGAUAAGGAUUGAGGAAUAUGACUGGAAGGAAUUACUAUUUAGCUAAGCUGACAAGGUCGCUUCUUAAGAUGACAUUUGGUUUCAGUAAUCUGACUAUUCUGUUUUCACUUUCAUCUUCUUUCUAAAUGAAAACAAAAGUGCUCCCUCCCUUCCUGGAAACCUCAGUAACACUAUGGGAAAAGUAGAACAUGACAUUGCAGCCUAUUGAUUUCUUCUUCCAGAUAGGUUUAAAGUACUCCUUAAGUUCUGACUAAAUAGAACUAAGCCUUAUUAAAAAUAACUGCCUCUUGUUCAUGUUAUCUGUACCUUCAGGGACCUGCCUUUCUUCAAGUAUUUCCUAGAGUAUCUAUUAUGAUACUGAAGAAGCUAAUUAUUUGUGUUGUAAAUGGGUAUAAAUGAAAAAAAAACAUACUGGUUUCUCUAGCCAGGAAAAAUGCUUUCUGGUGUAAUAUAUCUUGCUCCAGAACCCUCAUUCUAAUUGUAACACUAGGAUCAAAGAAACAAAGUCACUUUGUGGACCACAGCUAAACUGUGGAUAUUUUCCCAAAGACAUAAGAUUUUUAUGGCCCGAGCCUCUAGAAAGGAAGCCAUGUUUAGGAGCAACCAGCUUUCCUCCCAGCUUUAGGGGGCAGAGUUCCUGAGCCAGAGGACUUACUGUCCAGCUUUGAGAACCUCUCCAGAGUAUAUGCACUGGGUACUGCUCUUUUUCAAGAGAACCAAAUUAAGAGGAUGGCAAGAAACAGUAGAAGCACAGAGGAAAGACAACUCUGCAUGUGCCUGUGUGAAUGUGUGCAUCCAUGGAGUAUUUCCCAGGUAAAUACUAGUACUGGGGACAUAGGCUAAUUGUGUGUCCCACACUGCAAGAUGCUAGGGCGUAGUUAACACUGUGGUAUACAUACAAAUCAGGCACUGUCCAAAAGAUUUUUUAAAAUCUAAAGUCUGAAAUGUAAAAAUAUAAGGUCUCAACCCACUUUUACACUUUUAAAGAGAUCCCAUACCUGUUUCACUGACUGCCGUUAAUUACACUUUUGGAUCACAGCUGGUUAAAUUGAUAGAUUUCAGUUUAUCUCAGUGAAUUUUUAGAAUGGAGAUUAUAGCAUUUUUUAAUUGGAGAACAGACAUUUCCUAAAGUAUAUGAAAAAAAAUUAUUCACUGUUGGUUUAAACCAGUAUCUUUGUAUGAGUGCCAAAGAUAUAUGAACACAGAUACUGCCUGUGCAGACCUAAAUUUUAGUUUUGUGUACCUGGAUCCAUAUACAAAUUUUUUGUGGUUUAUAGCAUAAAAGCAGAACGUUGUUUCUUUCUUAGUUUUCAACCGGCUCAUCUUUUGUUUUUGUUUUUUGUUUUUUUGUUUUUUGUUUUUUUUGAGAUGGAGUCUUGCUUUGUUGCCCAGGCUAGAGUGCAGUGGCACAAUCUCUGCUUACUGCAACCUCCACCUCCGGGGUUCAAGUGAUUCUCCUGCCUCAGCCUCCUGAGUAGCUGGGACUACAGGCGCGCACCACCAUGCCCGGCUAAUUUUUGUAUUUUUAGUAGAGAUGGGGUUUCACUAUGUUGGCCAGGCUGGUCUCGAACUCCUGACCUCGUGAUCUGCCCACCUCAGCCUCCCAAAGUGCUGGGAUUACAGGCGUGAGCCGCCAUGCCCGGCCAAUUUUCAACUGGCCCAUACUUUAUAGUGAUGGAAAGCGCAUAAACUACUUGUAAAUCAUUAAAAUAGGGUGAUAACUGUGAUAAUAGUGUUUCUUGCAUUCUAGAAAAUUAUUUUAUUAACUACAUUCAAAACCCAGCAUUUCACAGGUUCCAUCAUUAGAAACAGUAUAGUUCUAGUUAACAUGAUUGGAGAGUUUCAGGGGAAAGGUUUACAUUUUCUGAAACUGUAUUUGGUAUGUGACUCAAUGUGGUAUUUCAGUCUUGUUAGUCACUUACAUGACUGACGUUUGCAAGGAUUUAUUGCCAAGUAAAAUUUGACCAGAGUGCACUGAGAAUAGCUACAUAAGGGGAAAUCUCUCAAAAUUCCUUCUGUUCAUUUAAUUUGGAGCAUAUUGUUUAAAUCAUUUUAAACAUAUGUAAAAAGUUGAAGCAUUAAAAAAUCUUCAAGAAACAAUGAAAAAAUAGAAAUUAGCAAACAUAAGUUUCUUAAUGCAAAAUUAAUAGUGAAUAAAAUAUAGCCUACAUUAAAAGCCAGAGGCUUUGCUAUAAAUAUAAGAGUUUAGAAAAACAGUGUGCUUCAAUUAAGGACUAAAUUAUCAAAACUGCAUGUUUGUUUUUUCUUUUCUUUUCUUUUUUUUUUGAGAUGAAGUCUCACUCUGUUGCCCAGGCUGGAGUGCAGUGGUGCGAUCUUGGCUCACUGCAACCUCUGCUUCCCAGGUUCAAGCGAUUCUCGUGCCUCACCAUCCCGAGUAGCUGGGAUUACAGGUGCACCACACCAUGCCCAGUUAAUUUUUGUAUUUUUAGUAGAGACAGGGUUUCAUUAUUUGGCCAGGCUGGUCUCGAGCUCCUGAUCUUAAGUGAUCCACUCGCCUCGGCCUCCCAAAGUGCUGGGAUUAUACACAUGAGCCACUGUGCCCAGCCUAAAACUACAUGUUGAAGCUUCCGGUCAUUUCCAUUAUUAUCCUUCUUUUGAAAUUCAAGUUAGUGCUUUUUAACCAAAUAAAAGAAGAACCAGCUCUUGGGAUAUGUGACUCUGCCUCUGUAUAAAGUGACUGGAAUUUUGUUAAAACCGUGUUUCCACUUCUGAACCCUGUUACCAUUCCCCCUCACAAAUCCCCACCCAACACCUGGAUUUUAAAGAUCCUCCAGUGUCAAGGGAAGCCACAGAGUCUAUUAAAGAGGCAGUUCUGAACCAAUUAAUUUUUGUCCUUAUAAUUUAGAGCAUUAAAUAGCUAAUAUAUUUAAUGGCACUAAUUGUUGUUCACGGCUUUCAUCAUACUUUUAAACAGAAUCCAAAGUAUUCAAAGGAAAGUAAGCGAAGUUAUCCAAAGCCAACUUUGUUUCAGGUGUGUCCCCUGCCCCAAAUAGAUUUUAGGGCAGAAAUAGAAAACUGAGUUUACACAGAACUAUUUUUGGAAAAGCUGCACUGGAGUAGAUGGAUUCUUCUUCAGCAUACUUUUUUGUUUGUUUGUUUGAGAUGGAGUCUUGCUUUGUCACCCAGGCUGGAGUGCAGUGGUGUGAUCUCCACUCACUGCAACCUCCACCUCCCAGCUUCAAGUGAUUCUCCUGCCUCAACCUUCCAAGUAGCUUGGAUUACAGGCGUGCGCCACCACAGCUGGCUAAUAUUUGUAUUGUUAGUAGAGACAGGGUUUCACCAUGUUGUCCAGGCUUGUCGAACUUCUGACCUCACGUGAUCCACCUGCCUCAGCCUCCCAAAGUGCUAGAUUAUAGGCGUGAACCACUGCGCCCGGCCAGCAUGCAUUUUAAAAGUGGCUUAGAUUUAGUUUUAAAUAUUUUGGGGUGAAAGGCAGGAACAGUUCUGUUUUUGACAUACAGGUUUUCUUUGGGAUUGUUUUCAUUUUCAAGUAUAGAUUCAUGUCAGAAUGGCCAACUUAACGUGGGUUUCUGUAUUCCCUGGUGUUGCUCUUAACCUGAACUCAUAAUCAGUUGCCAUACUGAGGCAAGAGCACUCAGGGUGAACAUAGUCAAGUUACUUUAAAAGUGAUAAAAGUGUUUUUCCAUGGUGAAACCUUCAGUAUUUGGCUGAAUGUAAAGUAUGUUGAAGUGGUAUAUUGAUGGUAAGUUGUUAAUCACUAACCUUGUUUGCACUUUUGUACACCACUGCUUGCACUAGGAUCUUGGUGUGAAUUUUCAAUUGUUUUACAGUGUAUACAGAUUAUUAAGGAUAAUUUAUAUAAAGAUGUUUCUGUUUAACUUUGUGUGUUUUACAACAAAGAGCUAUAAUAGAUGGUUAAACGUUUUUGAAUUGUGUUUAUAUGUUAGUUUGAUUAUGUUCUAUUAUCUUUUCACCUGCCAUGAAUUUGAGUGUUAGGAAGGGAAAAAUAAAAUACUAAUCUGGUCUUGAAGAA